GUGUGUGUUUCCCCUGCCGCGGGGAAAUGGCUGCUGUUGCUUCUGGGCCAGAGGAAGAGAAUGAGGUAGAGUGUUCUUUUGCCUCCGAGUAGGACCGAGAGUGUUGGGAAGAGGAGCGCGUCCCCGGGGAAAUGAGGGGGAGAGGCGUGUACGCGCCGCCGAGCUGAGGAGCUGGGUGAGGAAGAGGAAGUUACUGGAGCUGUCAUCCUGCUUAACUCGGUCGGCUAUUGAGCUUAGACUGUUUAGGUGGAUUGUGUUCAGGGAGUUUAGCUGAGCCGUUUGUACACAUUGGAAGCACAGUGUUACAUUUUACCGUAUUGCCUCUAGUUAUCUUGUCAAUCAAGAUAGGCUCAACAAACAUGUUUUCCUCAGUCUCCAAAAACUAGAUCAAGCAACCUCUGUUGUCUACUCAGUAUGUGCUGCUGGAAAGCUAUUUUGAGAAUAGCCUAAGCAAAACCCAGUUGUAAAGAUAAACCUGCUGCCAAUAGGUCUACAGUACAUUUCAGAACCAAAUACAAAUGGCAUUUGGAUAAUUAUUUGCUAAUGUGCUUUUCUACUCCAACCUCAUUACAUUUGUAUGUAGUUAGAUCAUUUAGCUAGAACCGUGCUGUGGAUAAAAGCAUAAUACAGUUUCGAUCCUUGUAGGCCGUACUCUGUGUCAUGGCCAGAGAUUGCUCUUUGCACCUGGUCUCACAAAGAAAUAGUGUAUGCUGUUCACGGGGAAGUGGAGGGAAGAGAAGGAGGGGCGAAGAGCUGUUCUCUAUUACCACUACUGGAAAAACAAUUUAACAUACGUAGUUAGUGGGAAAAGGACUUGUUUUACAGACUUCAGUUAGCCUCCCAGCUGUGUGAUUUUUCCUUAGCUGUUUGACCUUAGGUAACAUAUCUAUAAGCCACAGUUUUAUCAGUCACAGAGAGCUAAUACCUUUAUAGUAAGGUCGUUUUGAGAAUAGAAUGAGAAAACAUAUGUUUGGCAUGUAGUAGAUGCUUAGUUAAAUUUUAGUUCUGCCUCCUGCAGCCCUGACUAUGGGCAUUGAAGAACCUUUGCAAACACAAAUAUGAUUAAUUAUUUAGAGCAAUAUUAAGUAACUAUAACGUAAAAAAGACAAUGGAAUCUUUCAGAGCCCUUCAGUAUACAAAAGGUAUAUAUAUAAACUUUAAUGUAUAUAAGAAGUUUUUUUCUAAUAAUAAAAAUAGUCAUUAAAAUAGCCUAGUUAUUUAUAAAAAUAGUCAUACUUAAUUUUUUUUUCAUAUUUUCAAAUAGACCAUCUCUCAGUUUCAUUAUUCUUUAUGAUUUUCGUUUUGUAGCCCUGGAAAAAAAUUUUCAACCUCUAUAUAGCACAUGUAUGUUUCAAUACAGUUAAACAUUAAAAAGGAUCAAGGAACCAAAAUUUAGAUAGAUCCCCAAAGUUUAAAUGCUACGAAAAAUGCUAGCUCAUGUUGACUGAUUUGGUAAAUAAAACUUCUUAGAAUAUUUCUCUGAAUAUAAGGUAAAAUCCUCUGUCCACUUAAUUUUCAAUAACUUUCCAUUUUUAGUAUUUUCUCUGGAGUAGGAAAUGUGUUCAUUAAAUUUUAACUGCUGUGUGGAAAAAAUAAUGUCAUGGAGAGGUAUGGAAUUUAAGGUAAAGAUAACAGAAAAGUUAACAUAAAGAUUGUUUUCUUUUUGUUUUGGGAAAAGACAGGACAGAGAAUGUGGGAGUUUGAUUGGUUUAAGUUUGUCAUGGCCCUAUUUACAAAUGCCGGGUUUCCCAGUAGGGCUUACGUAAUUUAUUUGUAUCAAUAAUGAUAAGCUUUAAAAAAUAUUAUUUUCUAAAAUUCAAACUAAAAUUUCAACACAUUCAGUAUAGCUUUUAUGCAUAUUUUUAUAUAAAAAUUUCUGUGAAGGUAAGAGUCACAGGAUGGGGAGGGGGAAGCUCUCAUCAUUGAGGGGCUUGAAUUUUUAUAAAUAACUAGGGGCAACUAUUAGAAUGCAAAUUGUGAUUUUCUUAAAGUGUGUGUUGUGGGAGUGUGUAUUUACAUUGAACAGAAUCUUCUGCCAUGUGGUUAUAUUUAAAGGAAUAAUUCUUACCUUAAAACUAUAAAUGAUACUUUUUAAUACCUUAGAAACAAAGAAAUAGAAAUGAAUCUGCUCUUAUUUAGUAUUUGGUAAAGUAAUUUUCAUUGGACUUUAUGAAUUAUUUUAAAAGACUUUAUAUAUAUAUUUUUUAAUUUGGGAGAAUUGGGAAGAACAUUUCCCUGUAGUAAUCAUGAAAACAGAUGAUAUUGAACUAUAAAGAUAUUUGGAUAUGAAGUGGAAGUACUAAGGUUAUUAUUUAGACUAAAGGAAUUAUGUUACAACAAAAUCAAGGUGGAAACUUGUUUAGAUUUUAAAAGUUAAUGUUACUUAAAUGGGCUUUUAAGCAAUCUUUCCAAAAUAUCUGUUAUUAAUGUCUUUAAUUUGGGAGAAUUGGAAUACUUAGGAAUUUCUGUAUGUAUUACUUUGGGUAAUGCUAAUCAGAGUAAUAAAUACAUUCCAAAAUUUCAAAGAAGUUUACUUGCUUUCAUGACAGUUCCAGUGCAGAUGUUUACUUGCUUUCAUGACAGUUUACUUGCUUUCAUGACAGUUCCAGUGCAGGUGCUCCUGGUUAGCAGGUUUCUUGUGGCUUUCCUCUUAUGUUGUUUAGGGACUCAUACAACUUAGAUCUUGUGACUCCACCAUUUCUUAGGGCCUUGGAGUCCUCCCUAUUGCCUGAAGACCAUUUCUUAAGAAACUCCAGACUUAAAUGACAAACAUUCCUCCAAAUUUUAUUGGCAAGAUUUGUCACAGAGUCUUAUUUGAAUGCAAGGGGAGUGGGAAAUGUCCCUGGCAGGUGGAAAGCUUGGCCAUCUCUGCUACAAGGGGCAUUUCAUGGUGUUAUUUUAGAUGUUAGCAUAUAUUUAUGAAAUUACAUCCAAAAGGUGAAUUAUGAUAGUUAGGAAUUGCUUUCCAUCUUCAAAGAGUAAAAUUGGGUGUGAGUGGAGAGUGGUGGGGAGAGGAGAAAGGAGGGAAGAGUCACAGGAGUGGGAGGGGGAAGCUCUCAUCACUGAGGGGCUUAAAUGACAAGUGAGUUUCUGUAACUAUUUAAAGAUAUAAAUUUUUCAGAGAACAUUACAGUUGGAUUCUGUAACCUUUAGUGGGUCUCUCCUGUAGUAUCCAGUUAUUGAUUGUCAUUGUGCUUUAAUGAGUUCUGGCAGUUUGAGUUAUUUCUCUUUGUAUUUUGAAAUCAGUUCAGAUCAGUAGGACAAAACUCUGAAUUUCAGUUUCUGGGUAUAGUUUCAUAGGAAACACAUUUUUUGAAUUUUCUUCCUCUGUUAUUGGGAUAGGUGAUGAAGAUUACUUUAUACUUUGAGGGAAAUCUCAUUUAGGUGGACCUUACCAUAUUCUCUUGUUUGUUGCUGCAGUUUUUAUAAUUCUAAAGUUAUUAAAAUUAAUACAUGUGAGCCUUAACCCAGAAAGACCAAUAAAAUCAUCAAGUAAACAACAGAGGCUUAAUUAUUAAUUUGUGCUCAUGCUUUGUGAUGAAAAUACUACAACUUUCUUUUACUAACUGCACUGACACUGGACCUCUAAUACAGUAAAUGGUAUUUUAUCACUGGACAACUUUAAUUGAAUCACAAUUUAUUCUAUGAUUGUGCAGGUUUAUUAUAAUGUGAAACUUCAGCUCUGUGUCACCUUUACUUAUUUUUUAUUCUAAGAGUUUGGUUAGGGAUCUCUGGGGAGUUAUAUAUAAUCUCUUUAUUUCCCAAAGGGAAGAUUUUGGAAUAGUCUGGUUAACUUCUCCAUGGUAAAUACUUCUCUAACAUCUUGCAUCUUGAAAAUUGAAAACCUAAUCUGAGGACCCACUGUGCACCUAUUAUUGUACCCAGUUCUAAAGAGAAGUAUGAAAGAUGUAGAGGCUUAUAGUUUGUGAGUAAGGGAAAUAAAGCAUGUAAUUUAGUUAUUUCAAAACAAAUGAACUAGUGCAAGUCAAUAUGAUAUAAACUGUUUAUAGACAUUCUGAGACAUAAAAUGGAAUGUCAAUUGGGUCAGGAAUUACUUAAAGGGUUGCUUUUUUUUGGACAACUUUUAUGAGGUAUAAUUUAGAUACCUUAGAAGUAUCCAUUUAAAUUGUACAACUCAGUAGUUUUUAGUAUAUUAACAAUUGUGCAACCAUCACCAUAGUUAAUUUUAGAACAUUUUCAUUACCUAAAAUAUAAAUCCUGUAUCUUUCAAGAGUCACCCUUCAUUCUCUUAUGCCCCUAGUUCUAGGCAAUUACUACUUCCUUUCUCUAUAGAUUUGGCCAAUUUUGGACAUUUUGUACAAAUGCAAUCUUAAUAUAUGGUCGUUUAUGAUAAGCAUAUUUCACUUACCGUGUUUUCACGGUUCAUCCGUGUCAUAGCAAGUAUUUCAUUCUUGUAAUGGCUGAAUAGUAUGUCAGCAUAAGAAUACACCACAUUUAUCUUAUUCAUGAGCUGAUGGACAUAGACUUUUUGGCUAUCAUUAUAAAUCAUGCCGCUGUGAACAUUCAUGUACAAGUUCUUAUGUAUGUAUGUUUUGAAUUCUUUUGGGUGUGUACCUAAGAGUGGAAUUGCUGGAACAUAUACCACUUUGUGUUUAAACUUUUGAGGAACUUCUAGACUGCUUUCCAAAGCAGUCGCAGUAUUUUACAUUUCCAUCAGCAGUGUAUGAGAGCUCUAAUUUAUCCACUUCAUGCCAACAAUUGUUAUUAUCUCCUUUUUUCAUCAUAGUUCUUCUAGCAGGUGUGAUUUGAUCCUGGUUUUGAUUUGCAUUUCCCUGAUGGCUAAUGAUGCUUUUUAUGUGCUGUUGGACAUUUGUAUAUCCUCUUUGGAGAGAAGUGUGUGAAAAGACUCAAAUUCUUUGCCCAUUUUUAUAAUGAGUUUUUUAAUUAUUGAGUUGUAAGAGUCUUUUUUAUACUCUAGAUGUGUCCCUUAUAUAUGAUUUGCAAAUAUUUUCCUCCAUUUUGUGAGUUGUCUUUUCAUUUUCCUGAUGGUGUCAUUUGAGGCACAAACGUUUUUAGCUUGAUGAAGUGAAAUUCUUGUUAUUAUUUUUGCUGUGCUUUUGGUGUCGUAUCUAAGAAAUAAUGACUUCUUGUUUCUAAUCUAGCUAAUCUAUCUAAUAUAUCUAUUUCUAAUCUAUAUCUAAUCUAUUUCUAAUCUAUCUAAUAUAUCUAAUCUAAGGCCACAGAUAUUUACUUCCCUGUUUUGUCCUGAGAGUUUUAUAGCCUUAACUCUUACAUUUAGAUCUUUGAUCCAUUUUGAAUUAAUUUCUGUACAUGGUCUGUUGUAGAAGUCUAAUAUCUCUUUGCCUGUGGGUACUUAGUUGCCCCAGUACCAUUUAUUGAAAAGACUGUUCUUUCUCCAUUGAAUUGUAUCAUCACCCCUGUCCAAAAUUAAUUAACUGUAAGUGUGGAGGAUUUAUUUCUGGACUUUUAAUUCUAUUUCAUUGAUUUAUAUGUUUAUCCUUAUACUAGUAUGGUCUUGACUACUGUAGCUUUGUAAUUGAGAGGUCUGAGUCCUCAAACCUCUCAAAGUUUUUCCUUUUGAGAAGAAAAAAUGAAAAACUCUUUUUUUCUUUUUCAAGAUUGUUUUGGCUAUUUGAAUCUCUUGUGUUUCCAUAUCAAUUUUAGGAUCAGCUUGUCAGUUUCUGCAAAGAAGUCAGCUGGAAUUUUGAUGGGGAUUGUGUUAAAUCUGUACAUCAAUUUUGGGACCAUUGCCAUCUGAAUAUUAGGGCUUCCUGUCCAUGAACAUGGGAUGUUUUUCUAUUUAUUUAGAUCGUCUUUAAGUGUCAACAGUGUUUCAUAGUUUUCAGAAUAUAAGUUUCAUACUUCUGUUGCUGCAUUUCUUCCCAAGUAUUUUAUUCUUCCAGAUGAUAUUGUAAAUGGAAUUAAAAAAAAUUUGGGGGGUUUUUGCAUGACAAGUGCAUAAAAAUACACUUGAUUUAUGUUUGUUGAUCUCGUAUCCUCCAACCUUGCUGAAUUUCUUAGUUCUAAUAGUUUUUUUUUUCUUUUUUUUUUGAGAUGGAGUCUCACUCUGUCGCCCAGGCUGGAGUGCAAUGGCACUGUCUUGGCUCACUACAACCUCUGCCUCCUGGGUUCAAGUGAUUCUCCAGCCUCAGCUUCCUGAGCAGCUGGGAUUACAGGUGCCUGCCACCAUGCCUGGCUAAUUUCUGUAUUUUUAGUAGAGAUGGGGUUUCACUGUGUUGGCCAGGCUGGUCUUGCCGACCUCGUGAUCCACCUGCCUCAGCCUCCCAAAGUGCAGGGAUUACAGGUGUGAGUCACUGCACCCGGCCAGUUCUAAUAGUUUUUAAGUGGAUUCCAUAAGAUUUUCUACAUACAAAUAUCAUGUCACCUGCAAACAAAUGAAGUUUCAAUUCUGCUUUUCCAAUAUGGAUGCAUUUUAGUUCCUUUUCUUGCUUAAUUGCCCUGGAUAGAACCUCCAGAACAUUACUGAAAAGAAAUGUCAAGAGAAGUCACUUGAGUUGCAGCAAUCCUUGUCUUGUUCCCAGUCUUAGGGGGAAAACAUUCCAUCUUCUGCCAUUAAGUAGAUGUUAGCUGUGAUUUUUUUUUUUUUUUUUUUUAAACUGCUCCUUGCGGAGAAAGGCUAGCCCAUAGGCAGGCAGUGUGCGGAAAGUAGUGAGCUAUAAGUUUUUCAUUAAUAGCCUUUAUCAGGUUGAGGAAGUUCAUUUCCUAGAUUGUUGAGUGUUUGUUUGUGUGAGUGUGUGUGUUUGUGAGAGAGUGUUAGGAUUGAGUUUUGAGAGAAUUGUGAAAUGUGGAUUAGAAAAAUAAAGAUGCUAUGUCAGGUAAUAAGGGGCAGAUAAUAAUGCUUAUCUUGCUGGAGGAAGAGGGGCUAGAUUUUCCUCUUUUUCCCUCUCCCUUUCUUCCCCAUUCCUUUCUUGUUUUUGUUUUGAGACGGAGUCUUGCUCUAUCGCCCAGUCUGGAGUGCAGUGGCCUGAUCUCAGCUCACUGCAACCUCCGCCUCCCAGGUUCAAGUGAUUCUCCUGCCUCAGCCUCUUGAGAAGCUGGGACUACAGGCUAAUUUUUGUACUUUUAGUAGAGACGGGAUUUUGUACUUUUAGUAGAGAUCACUAUGUUGGCCAGGCUGGUCUCGAACUCCUGACCUUGUGAUCUGCCCGCCUCAGCUGCCCAAAGUGCUGGGAUUACAGGUGUGAGCCACCGCGCCCGACCCUUUCUUGAUCUUUAAUCAUCUUCCCAUCAGUCCACAUGCACAUUUGGAGAGCACUUAAUCUUUUACUGAUCUGUAUAAUUAAGAUUUUUUGAGCAGUGGAAGUAUCCUUUCUUUUGAAAAAUACUAAAAAUUGUGUGGAGAAUUUCUUACUGAAUAGCUUGAUAGCUAGGUUUGGAGGGCAUCAGAGAAGAUACUAAAUCAUAAAUGAAGUGCCAACCAUGGACUUACAAAGAAGUGAACACAGUGGAAUACUUCAGCCAUAAAGAAUGAAAUCCGUCUUCAAAAAGAAUGGAAUCCUGUCAUUCUUGGCAACUUGGAUGGAACUAGAGGACACUGUGUUAAGUGGAAUAAGCCAGGAACAGAAAGGUAAAACACCACGUAUUCUCACUUCUAGGUGGAAGCCAAAAAAAGUCGAUCUCUUAGAAGUAAAAAGUAGAAAAGAGGAUUCUAGAGGCUGGAAAGGGUAGGGGGAAGAGGGCUAGGGAGAGAGAUUGUUAAAGGGUACAAAAUUAUAGCUAGAUGGGGGAGUAAGUUCUAGUGUUCUGUAGCACUGUAGGAUGACUAUAGUUAACAAUAUUAUUAUGUAGUUUCAAAUAGCUAGGAGGAAAAUAUUGAAUGUUCCAAAUGCAAAGAAAUGAUACAUGUUUGAGAUGAUGGAUAUGCUGAUUACCUUGAUCUGAUCGCUACACAUUGUAUGUAUGGAAACAUCACUGUGUAUCCCAUAUAUAUAUACAAUUAUGUGCCAAUUAAAAAAUUUAAAAAGUAAGCAAACCUUUGCCAUAUUGGGGGUAUGGUUAAUAAAAAAUUUUAUGUUUAGUUUAAUGUACUUUGAAUCUAGCUGUCAGCUGACAUUCUCCCACCCUAAACAUUUCAGCAUCAAUGGCUUUGUUUUUACAAGUUUUCUUUAUAAUUUUCUAAAAAAUUUAACAAAUUUCAUAUGAAACUUUGCUCAGUAAGGUAAAGUUGUGUUUCACUUUGAUGUGGUGAUUACCCUUUGUUUACUUUUUGAAAUUUUAAUUGUGUUCCCAUGCAUCCACAUUCUGAUCAGAUAAAUAUUUUUAAAAAUUUUUAUUUUUGUCUUUCAUGUAUAGUUCUCAGAAGUUAAGAUAACUUUGAGUUUAGCUAAGAAUAUUCCUGUUAACAGGUGAAAUUGGAAAGUGGUAAUAGAAUUUUUGUUUUGUAACAGGUUUAUUAGUUUUCAUUAUUUUUAGUCCGCUUUAAAAUUUUGAUACAGAUACAAUUUAUUAUUAUUUUUAAAGAAAUAAGUAGUCUAAUAAAUAAGACAAAUGAGAAACUCGUCAUUUGUACUGAAUAGAUGCCUGGUAAUUUGGGGCUUUCAAAUAUUGUUUUCAUUUAUUAACAAUUGAAAUUGGUGACACAAAAUAGAGAUUAAAACACUUUAUGUUCCUUAUAUUCAUCUUUUGCAGAGAGAACCUCCCUCUCUAAUCUUAAAGUUUAAACUCUAUUUUUCUCUUUCCCAUAUUACUUAAAUAGAUUUCCUAAAUGAGUAACAUAAAUUAGAGUUACAUAAUACCAGCUACAAAUACUGCUAAAAGAAUAGAACUAAAUUUAGUAUAUCCCAACCUUAAUGUCUCUCUAUACAAAGACUUUGUUGGAAUCUCAUAUAUCCAUUGCUUUCUGAUCAUAAUGUUUAUCAUAUUUAACAAAGCAAAACUCAGAAAUUACUUAACAGGGUAUAUUCUUCUAUAGGUUCAUAUUUAGUACAAUCUUCUGCAAUAUCUACAUAUAAUUUUAUGAAACAACAUAAUGUGAGUUAUAUACAGAAUGGUAGCCUUGAAACACUGUCAGAAUUUGAAUCACCAAAAUAUAACCUGUUAAUUAAUAUUUAUUAAGCUUCUAUUUGUUAUAGACUAUUGUAUUCAGGGUUCUGGGGAAUAAAAAGAAAUGUAGAAUAAUCUUUCUACCAGGGAAUGGAGCUAAUAUUUUUUUGACUACUGAGUACCAAGGAAUGUGAAAAGCCACUCCCCUCCUUCCCUUUAAAUGUGUAAUCUAAAUUAUUCUUCAUGAAAAUCCUAUGAGAGAGGCAGUAUGAUUCUCAUUCUGAAGCUGGUUAAGAAAGUGAGCCUUGGGUCCUCCACUUUCCAGCUCUACGGAAACUCAUUUAACUUCUCUAUGCUUCAGUUUUCUCAUCUGUAAUAGGGAGAUAAUAUUCCUUAUCUCGUAGAGUUUUGUGAGGAUUAAAUGAUGUAGUCCUGUAAAGUAUUUAGGACACUACCUGGCACAUCUGUAGUAAAAAACCAAACUAAAAAACAAUACACGUACACUAUUACUGUUUCUUAUUAGGAAAGAAGUUAAUUAACGUGCCCAAGAUUACAACCAGAUCUAUUUGAAUUUAAAACACUCUUAUACUAUAAUGCUUACAUUUAUAGGAUGUUUAAGUCUGGAUCUAGUAAACAGGUGAAGGCAGAAUAUGCUAAGUGACUAACAUUAAGUGCUAUGACAUACAGAGUACAUAUGGAUUUUAAACUACAGGGAUAAGUAAGAGAGGAGAUAGAUGUUGCUCUUGCCUUUAUGAUGAGAAAAAAGGCAGGGAAAAAAUUAAUAGACUACUGUAAUAUCUUCCUUGCUAGUCUACAACUUCCAUUAUAUCUCCUUUAACAUCUUUUCCUUUGUACACAUUGUCACCAGAGAAAUCCUUGUAAAAUUCAUCCCACAUUGCUUAAAUUCUCUGCUUACAGUCCUUUAAUAAUAAUAGUUACUGUUUUCUGGUUACCUACUGUGGGCUAGGAUAGGAGACAGCAAGCUUCUCUUCUUUUCUCUUCUCUUUUUUUUUUUUUUUUUUUGAGAUGGCAGAGUCCCACUCUCACCCAGGCUGGAGUGCAGUGGCACGAUCUCAGCUCACUGCAACCUCCACCUCCCAGGUUCAAGCGAUUCUCCUGCCUCAGCCUCCCGAGAAGCUGGGAUUACAGGCGCACACCACCACACCCGGCUAAUUUUUGUAUUUUUAGUGGAGAUGGGGUUUCACCACGUUGGCCAGGCUGGUCUCGAACUCCUGACCUCAAAUGAUCCACCUGCCUCAGCCUCCCAAAGUGUUGGGAUUACAGGAAUGAGCCACCUCGCCAGGCCUAGCAAGCUUUUUUCUAUGAAGGGACAGAUGUAAAUAUUUUGGCUUUUUGGGUCAUGCAAGAUCUCUGUUGCAUAUUCUUUUUUGCUGUAAUUUUUUUGUUUUUUAACAAUCCUUUAAUUUUUGUUGUAAUUCUUUUUUCACAAUCCUUUAAAAAUGUAAAAACCAUUCUUUGCUGCCAAAUCAGUCUGGAUGCAGCUUAUUGACUGACCCCUAUGCAAGGAGAUUUACGUGAACUAACUCAUUUCUUCUUGUAACAAUCCUGGUAAAGUUGAUAUUAUUUCUACUUCACAGUUGAGGAAAUUGAAGCUUAGAGAGGCAGAUUUGAUGAAGGUCAAGUAAGUGACAGAUUGAGGCCAUUGGAAUACCUAAACCUGUGUACUUCCUAAGAUAUCUUGCUGCUUCCUAUUACUUUUAAAUAAGAUGCAAAUUUCUUAGCAUUAUGUGUAAGGCCCUUGAUGAUCUUGUCUUUGCUUACUUUUCUAGUUUUCGUAUUUGUUACUACUCUCUCUCACAUAUUCCCUAGCCUAGCUGUAGUGAGUGACUUACAGCGUGGUCUGUGCUUUAUAUAUGCCUACAAUACCUUAUACUUUAUGACCUCAUUGAUUUCUUUAAUAAUCUGCCUCUGGUACUUCCUACUUUGGGAAACCUUACUUGGUACUUGUAGUCCUUGCUUUAUGAACUUUUUCUGUGCUCCUCUAGCAUUCUGUGCAUUCUUCAUUCAUAACACUUACUACAUUGCCUUGUGUUUAACUUGGGUUUAUGUCUCCGUUUUGCGUUAGACUGUGAGUUUUUUUUUUAAGAGAUGGAGAUUUUGCUAUGUUGCCCGGGCUGACCUUGCAUUCCUGAGCUCAACAGAUCCUCUCCCUGUAGCCUUAGAUUGUAGGAUUUUUUUUUUUUUUUUUGAGAUGGAGUCUCACUCUGUCGCCAUGCUGGAAUGCAGUGGCGCGAUCUCGGCUCACUGCAACCUCUGACUCCCUGGUUCAAGCGAUUCUCCUGCCUCAGCCUCCCGAGUAGCUGGGAUUACAGGCACACACCACCAUGCCCAGCUAACCAAGGCAGGCGGAUCACCAGGUCAGGAGAUCGAGACCAUCCUGGCCAACAUGGUGAAAUCCCCUCUCUAUUAAAAAUACAAAAGAUUGUGAGGUUUUUAAGGGCAUAGAUGAUAUAUGCCUUACCUUUGUAGCUCAAGUGUUUGAUACAUAGUAGGGGCUUAAUACAGAGUUUGGCAUAUAGUUGGGAAUUUGAAAGUGUUUAUUAAAUGAAUGAAUAAUUAAAUGGCAUUACAGACAUGGAAAUCAUAUCAGCAGAUCUAUAGUUGCAGAAAAAUGAGUCCAGGUUCAGGGGUGGUGGUGAGUGGGAAAGUAAGUAAAUUUCUGGUUAACUUCUAGGGCUCGAGUGGGAACAUGAGGUUAAUAAGGCAAAUUGGAGAAUGAUCGUGGAGGGGCUUGAAUAUCUUGGUAAGGAAUUUUAAUUUUGUUCUGGAGUCAUUGAUACAAAGCUUUCAACUCUAGAGCAGCAGGUGUUUUUUAAAUCCAUAACUUGGGUUCUCUUAAUACACAAAUUGUAUGUUGUAAUAUUGCUUUAGGUAUUUUAUAGAACAUUCAUUACCUAAACAAUUGUUUUGAUUAAUAGAUACUGCAAGAUGUAGCUCUAGAAUAUCAUAAUUAUCAGUACUACUAUUAAAGACAUUGGGAACCAUGGAAUGAUUUUGAACAGGUUGGUGGCAGUUUGAAAUUAAUCUUUUUUUUUUUUUGAGACAGAGUUUUGCUCUUGUUGCCUAGGCUGGAGUGCAGUGGCACGAUCUUGGUUCACUGCAACCUCCGCCUCCCAGGUUCAAGCGAUUCUCCUGUCUCAGCCUCCUGAGUACCUGGGAUUACAGGCAUGCGCCACCACGCCCGGCUAAUUUUGUAUUUUUAGUAGAGAUGGGGUUUCUCCAUGUUGGUCAGGCUGGUCUCGAACUCCCAAUCUCAGGUGAUCCGCCGGCCUCAGCCUCCCAAAGUGCUGGGAUUAUAGGCGUGAGUCACUGUGCCCGGCCUGAAGUUAAUUUUUUAAGAUUAAUCUAGUUGAGGUAUUCACCAUCAGUUGAGGAGAUGGGACUGGGAAGAAGGAGGCCUUUUAAAAAAAGUUAAAAUAUAAAGUGAUAAGUCAAUGAUUGACUAUGAGGAAGUCAGAGACGAAUGAGAAAAACGGAAGAGGCAGGUCAAGGAAGGAAAUUGUGUAUUUUAUGUUGGUUAAAUUGAUUACUGUGAAUUCUAUUGGAGUGAUUUCUAUCGUUGCCUGAAUUUGGGCUCUGCUUACUUUAUGCUUGAAUAAUUAGAAUACUCUUAUGAUUGGUUUCCCUUCCUGUUGCUAAUUCAUGGAUUCUUAAUCUUUGGUGCUGUGGACCUUUCUUCAGUCUGGAGAAGGCUGUGAAUCCAAUGUAGAAUGACAAUUUUAAAUGAGUGAAAUAAAGUAAAUAGGACUUGAAAGGAACUUGUUAUAUUGAAAUGCCAAAAUAUGAUAUAGUAAUAUAUAUGCUUCUCUACUAAUACUGUUAAGUAACGUCUUGCAAUGAGUCUAAUAGCUACCAUAAUUUUGUAAUACUGGUACAUAUAGAUAUUUUGAGAUUUCUGUAACAACUAUAAUAUGAAAUGAAAAUGUACUUCUGUUAGUGACAGAAAUCACAGGUACUGCUAAUACUAUUAUGGUUGAUUGUUUAGGUUUGUGUGAAAAUUUUAGAGAUUAGUGAAAAUGGUGAUGUAAUUUUUUUUCUAUAUAAAUUCACAGGUUUCCUGAGAUUUAUGGAACCUAGGUUAAUUACCUUUGCUUGUACUAGCUCCUGUUUUACUCUUCUUCUGUGUAUUUUUGUCAUAGUAAUGUACUUUUCUUUGCAGAUGGUAGUAUUUUUAUUGCAUCAUGUCUGUUUUGGGAAAUAAUAUGUACUCUUUGUAAAAAAAAAUUCAAAUGGUAAUAAAACGCAUAAUUUUCUGGUUAUCCUGCUUCAUGGCGAUCAAGCUUGUUAGCAGUAUAAUAUAUACAGUAGUUUCUUGGUAUAGAGAGGAUUGGCUCCAUGACCCUUGUGUAUGCCUAAAUCCAUGCAUACAUACUCAGGUCCUGCCAUGUAUAUGAAAAAUUGGCCCUCUAUAUACAUGGGUUUCUCAUCUCACAAGUGCUAUAUUUUCCAUCUGUGUUUGGUUAAAAAAAAUCUCCACGAGUGAACCUGUGCAGUUCAAACCCAUGUUGUUCAAGGCUAAGUGGUAGUACUGUUACCUGUUUCUGGUCAAUAUAUACUUACAUAACCACAAAAACAUAACUAAAAUAGGUUCAUACUGUGUAUACUUUUUUAAAAAUUUGCUUUUUUUUCAUUUGAAAACAUCUUUUUUCAUUAAUAAAUACACCUCAUGCUUUAAAAAAUUGUAGGAUGAAAGUUGAGAUAUGUAUUACAUAACACAAACAUUCACCAUUUUAAAGUGUAUAUUUUAGUGGUUUUAGUACAUUCAGUAUGUUGCCAACCACCACUACAAGCAAAUUCCAGAACAUUUCCAUCACCCACAAAAGAAACCUCAUAUUUUAUGUCAGUUAGUUCCAGUUACCCCAUCCAUUGACAAUUUCUGGUCUACUUUCUGUCUCUAUGGAUUUGCUUCUUCUAGUCAUUUAAUAUAAGUAGAAUCAUAUAAUAUGUGACUGUGUCUGCUUUUUUCACUUAGCAUAAUAUUUUCAAGAUUCAUGUUGUAGCAUAUAACAGUAUUUCAUUCCUUUUUUUUUUUUUUUGAGAUGGGGUCUUGCUGCAUCACCCAGGCUGGAGUGCAGUGGCACGAUACCGGUUCACCACAGCCUCCGCCUCCCAGGUUCAAGCAGUUCUCCUGCCUAAGCCUCCUGAGUAGCUGGGAUUACAGGAGCCCACCACCACGCCUGGCUCAUUUUUUGUAUUUUUAGUAGAGACGGUGUUUCACCAUGUUGGCCAGGCUGGUCUCAAACUCCUGACUUCAGGUGAUCUGCCCACCUUGGCCUCCCAAAGUGCUGGGAUUACAGGCAUGAACCACUGUGCCCGGCCAAUAUUUCAUUCCUUUUUAUGAGUGAACAAUAUAUUAUUAUACAUACUUGGUUAUUAUAAAUAAUUCAUGUAUAUGGUUUUGUGAAGACGUAUGUUUUCAUUUCUCUUGGGUGUAUACCUAAGAGUGGAAUUGCUGGGUCAUACGUAUUUCUGUGUUUUAACUUUUUGAGGAAUUGACAAACUUUUCCACAGUAGCAGCGCUGUUUUACAUUUCCACACCUCACGCUUUUUUCUUUUUUUUUUGAGACGGAAUUUCGCUCUUGUUGACAGGCUGGAGUGCAAUAGCAUGAUCUCGGCUCACUGCAGCCUUGGCCUCCCGGGUUCAAGCGAUUCUCCUGCCUCAGCCUCCCGAGUAGCUGGGAUUACUGGCAUGUGCCACCACACCCGGCUAAUUUUGUAUUUUUGGUGGAGAUGGGGUUUCUCCAUGUUGGUCAGGCUGGUCUUGAACUGCCGUUCUCAGGUUAUCUACCUGCCUCGGCCUCUCAAAGUGAUGGGAUUAUAGGCAUGAGCAACCGCACCUGCCCUACCUCCUGCUUUUUAAUGGCUUCAUUGUAAUCCAUUUUAUUGAUGUCCUGUCAUUCAGUCCCCUGUUGAUUGACAAUUUAUUUCUGUAUUUUUGAUGAUUAUCAACACUAAUGCAGUGAAAAAACUUGUAUAAACACCUUUUGCACACUUUUUUAAAGUAUAAAUUUUUAGGAAAGGAAUUGCUGGAUCAAAGUAAUUACACAUUUAAUAUUUGAUACAUCUUGUCAGAUUGCCCUUUAGAAAUGUUUUAUAAAAUUUUACUCCCAACAAUUGUGUGAUGUAUGCUUAUUUUCUCAAACUCAUAUUCACAUAAUUAAUUUUUGUCAUUUUAAUAACAAAAAGUCAUACAUAUUUUAAAUUUUGGAAUUUGUUAAUUAUAGUGGAGAUAAUUUUUUUUUUCACAUUUUUUUUGGCCACUGCAUUCUUUUGUGAUUUGCCUGAUCAUGACCUUUACCCUAAAUUUUUCUAUUGGGUGUCUCUGUUUUUCUUAUUACUUUGUUAAUAGCUGUUUACAUUUUAGAAACAUUACCUUAUUGCUCAUUAUCAAUAUUGCAGAGACUUUGUUCCAGUUUCUUGUUUGUUUUUUGACUUUGUUUAUGACUUUGCUCUUUGCCUUAUAGACAUUAAAUUUUUAAAAUACUGUUUAUCAUUCCUUAUAAAAGGUCUUUGCCUUGCUUAGAAUAAGUUUUCUGCACCCCAAGAUUAUAAAAUAUUUUCUCCGCAUUUUCUUCUGGGAAUGUCUAAAAUUUGGCAUGAUUUAGUAGAAGCUUGGUUUUUGUAGUUGGUCUUAACUAUGUUCAGAUUCCCGUCUAGCCACUUACUAGCUGUGAGGUGUUAGAUGUCUGCACAACUUCUCUGUAUCUCACCUUCCUCAUCUGUAAAAUGAUAGUUGAUAAUUAGGGUCUAUGCUUUUGGUUAAGUUAAAUGCAAUAAUUCAAAUUCUCUAGCAUACCAUCUGGCCACAUACUGGGUGUUCAGUGCAUGUUUUCUUUUCUCUCUCACCCAUAAACUCCAUCUUCUAUCAGUCUAGUUAAAAUCUGGUCCAGAAGAUAAGGGAGGGGAAAGUUUCAAGAAAUAAUGUUGCCCUUAGUUUUCAAAGUCAGAGAAGCCAUGUGGGAUGAGUACUGUCUGAAAAGGAGAUUGAAAAUUCAUUUAGUAAUUAGGAAGUAAUUUAUGUUUAAUGAAAACAUUUUUUAGUAGCAUGAUAAGAGGCAUAUUUUAAUACAAAGAAGACUAAAACCUAUAUAACAUACCUAAAGGAUAUGUGCAUAUGCAACAUGUAUCCAUCAUGAUUUGUAAUAUUUGGGAGAAAUAGUUGUAACUCUACUCUUCUUAUUGUUGGAAUACUGGUAAGAGGAUAGAGAAUCAAUGCUGACAUACAGUAUAUUUAUAUUGUAUGUAUAAGGUGUACAUAAAUUUAGGUAAUUUUUACUAUUAAUAGUUACAAAUUACUGUAUUUGUAACACACCUCACAAUCAUCAACCUGUAUUAGAACUACUGCUCCAUUGGAAUCUUCUUAGUAGCAUUAUAAUGGACUUUAAUGGAAUUUACACAUAUUCUUCACUAAAUUAAAAUUAUGUAUAAACUGUUAUAUUUCUUUUGGGGAAAGCAACUUUAAAUACAUUUUAGAAAGAAAUGGGAAAUAAAUGUUUACAACAUGGUAGUCAUUGUUUACAUUUUUCUCAUCUUGUUUCCUGGACUAUGAGGAUUUUAGGACAGGGGGACAUAGUUUUUGCUAUAUUGCCCAGGCUGGAAUACAGUGGCUAUUCACAGAUGUGACCAUAGUUUGCUAUAGCCUCGGGCUCCUGACUUCAAGCAGUCCUCCUGCCUCAGCUUCUGAGUAGCUGGGACUACAGGCACAUGCAAGGUGCAUGGCUUAUAAUGGGUUUUUGAUAAAUAUUUAUAAAAUGUUUCAUUCUCCCCCCCCCCCAAUUUUUAUCUUCUGGUAAAAUAACUUCAAAAUAAAGGUUUUAAAAUUUGUUAAGAAAAAUAAAUAUUCCUCAAGUGGAGUAAUAAUAGACAUGGAUUCUGUGCAAUUUGUUUUCAGAAAAUUAUAUCAAACUGUAUUCCUUGACUCUUAGUAACUGUCUAAAAAUUUUUUUUGGUAUGUUACAUGUAUACUGUCAUUAUUUUGUCAGCUUCAAAACAAGAAGGAAAUUAUUCUGUAUUGGUUAGCUCAGGAGGAAGGUAAUGAGUUUUAAGUAACAAAACAGGAAAUUAGCUCCUCUGUGACCUUUGAUGAGUUUGUGAAGCUGGCGUUGUGAGUGCAGGAUUGAAAUUGUGAAGAGCAUUAUAUUUAGUUUGCUUUGUUGCUUUUGCAGAGUAUCUAUUUGCCAGGAAAACCUAGGAAUUGAAGUUAAAGACUCUGCUACCUUUGUGGGAAAUGAACAAUACUCUUCCUUCUGCUGGCAAAAUCUGGGUGUCUACUUUUCAGUGGCUGGUUUUUGCUUUCACGUAGGGUCAGAGUAUCCUUUUCCUGGAACCAAGCUUGACUCAAAGCCAUUACUAAUAGGGAUGCCAAAGGAAAAAUAUGAUCCUCCAGAUCCUCGCAGAAUUUAUACCAUCAUGUCAGCAGAGGAGGUAGCCAAUGGGAAAAAAUCUCACUGGGCAGAAUUAGAAAUCUCGGGUAGAGUGCGGAGCCUAAGUACAUCACUUUGGUCAUUGACACACUUGACAGCGCUGCACCUAAAUGACAAUUACCUUAGUCGCAUUCCACCUGAUAUUGCCAAGCUUCAUAAUCUGGUUUACCUGGAUCUGUCAUCCAAUAAACUCAGAAGUUUACCAGCAGAACUAGGAAACAUGGUGUCUCUCAGGGAAUUGCUUUUAAAUAACAAUCUGUUACGGGUUUUGCCUUAUGAACUUGGUCGGCUCUUCCAGCUACAAACUCUAGGUUUGAAAGGCAAUCCUUUAUCACAGGAUAUUCUCAACUUAUACCAGGACCCAGAUGGAACCCGAAAGCUACUGAACUUCAUGCUUGACAAUCUCGCAGUUCAUCCAGAGCAGCUUCCUCCGAGGCCAUGGAUUACAUUAAAAGAACGAGACCAAAUUCUGCCGUCAGCAUCAUUCACGGUUAUGUGUUACAAUGUGUUAUGUGAUAAAUACGCUACCCGGCAGCUAUAUGGCUAUUGCCCAUCCUGGGCAUUAAACUGGGAAUACAGGAAAAAGGGAAUUAUGGAAGAAAUUGUUAACUGUGACGCAGAUAUCAUUAGUCUUCAGGAAGUGGAAACAGAGCAAUACUUCACUCUCUUUCUGCCAGCAUUGAAGGAGCGUGGAUAUGAUGGAUUUUUUUCUCCAAAGUCACGUGCCAAAAUCAUGUCUGAGCAGGAGAGAAAGCAUGUAGAUGGUUGUGCAAUAUUCUUCAAAACAGAAAAAUUUACAUUGGUGCAGAAGCAUACAGUGGAAUUUAACCAAGUGGCGAUGGCUAAUUCAGAUGGAUCCGAAGCUAUGCUGAACAGAGUGAUGACAAAAGAUAACAUUGGUGUCGCUGUGGUAUUAGAGGUCCACAAAGAACUAUUUGGAGCAGGUAUGAAGCCUAUUCAUGCUGCAGACAAACAGCUGCUUAUAGUGGCAAAUGCCCACAUGCAUUGGGACCCAGAGUAUUCUGAUGUGAAGCUCAUCCAGACCAUGAUGUUUGUCUCAGAGGUUAAAAACAUUCUGGAGAAAGCCUCUAGUAGGCCUGGAAGCCCAACUGCAGAUCCUAAUUCCAUCCCGCUGGUGCUAUGUGCAGAUCUUAACUCAUUGCCAGAUUCAGGUGUUGUGGAAUACUUAAGCAAUGGAGGAGUAGCUGACAACCAUAAAGACUUCAAGGAACUAAGGUACAAUGAGUGUCUUAUGAACUUCAGCUGCAAUGGAAAGAAUGGAAGCUCAGAAGGGAGAAUCACACAUGGCUUCCAACUUAAGAGCGCCUAUGAAAAUAACUUGAUGCCUUACACCAAUUACACCUUUGAUUUCAAAGGCGUGAUUGACUACAUUUUCUAUUCCAAGACUCAUAUGAACGUGCUUGGUGUCCUGGGGCCUUUAGAUCCUCAAUGGCUGGUUGAGAACAACAUCACUGGGUGUCCACACCCUCACAUCCCUUCAGACCACUUCUCACUGUUAACACAACUUGAACUCCACCCUCCACUCCUGCCUCUUGUCAAUGGUGUUCACUUGCCUAAUCGGAGGUAGUGGAGUACUGCCCCGCCAAGACGGGGAUCUGUUGCUAUGGACCUGUACAGUUGUAAAUCAAAGUAUGUAGGAGUGAAGUAUGGCCAUCCUUAAGCUGCUUCUUCAGGUUUCUUUCAUUAUGUGUUUGCUGUAAGACUUUGUACAUUUUUGUGCAUAUUGGUAUCAUUUGGCAGUAGGGCUGGAACCAAAGUAUUACUCUCUUUACAAAAUUUUAAUUUAACAUGUUUUUAAAUUGGACCUUCUUUAUAUUGUAUUAACAGCCAGCAUUCAAAAUUGAUAAAUUACCAAUUUGAGGCCCAAUAACAGUGUAUUUGUUUUUCCAAAACAAAUACUUUCUUUUGAAUGGUUUCAGUGAGCCAACCAUUUUAUAAAAGGCAAUUUUUAAAAACUAUAAAUACAGUAUUUUAAACUGAAUGAUGAUAUGCCUUCCAGGGAAAACCUUGAAUUUUUCCUUUAUAACUGACUUUUGGAUUCCAAAGUCAUUUGCACAUUAACAGAGUACUUAAAUUUACUUGUUCAGUCCAUAAACUAUGAUAUAGCCUCUAUACAUGGUAAGAAAAUUUGAAAAAUUAAAGAUGGUUGCACAGUAUACUUUUAUAAUCCAGCAUGUAACACCACAUGACAAUUUGUUGGCCAAAUGCUGGUUUGGAGUUUUUUUGAGGAAUCACUUUGGUUUUUUUGUCCUUUAUAUAUAACCUUAUUGGAAGUAUUAAUUCUAAGCCUGUCUCUCAAGUUUAUUUAUAGAGAAAAAGUAAGUAAUCUGUAUUGCCACAUACCUUGAAAAUAGAAUGUGGUAUGUUUAGGAUGCCCACGGAAUGAAUUUUUCCUUAUUCCAAUUCAACCUUCUGUCUGGUUGUGCCAGGAAAACAGAUGUUAUAUGACCUAUGUCAUUUUUGCCAUUAUAGUCAAAUGUUAAAAGAAGAAAAAAGUCUGCUGAAUAAAAAGGCCUUGAUCAAAGUUUCAGAUGGGGAAAAUCAUACAGAUAUUUUAUGUGUUUCCAACAUAGAUUAUGUGGCUGUUGGUUUCUUGAGAUGACAGUGCAAAGGAUUUGGGAGAGAGAACAAAUUUGGGGCAGUAGUUGAAAACGUUGGGUCAUUUUCCUGACUCUAGCUGCCAAAUGGCCAUCAUAUGCUUUUAAUCUUUGUUUCAGUUGUCUGUCAGGGUUGAAUUAAGAAGCUACUGGUUUAUUCCCAAUUGUUGAUGCCUUUAGGUAUGUUGGAAUCUUUUUUUUGCCUAGGAGGGGCCAGUUGAAAAUCUGUGACUCAAGAGGCAGUGAACAGAAUACUGUUUUCUGGGGAAAAAUUGGUUGGCUACUUGAUGUUAAUUAUGGCACAGUAACAGGAAAAGGUUGUGUCUGUGUUUUUAAGUUUUUCUUUAUUCUGCUUUUUUGCUGCUAUAAGAGUUUUCUGAAAUUUAUAUUUUAAACUUUUCAUGCACUUUACUGUUUCUAGUCUCAAAAUGUGAUAUUUUUAAUAAACAAGAAAUUUUCCAUUAUGUGAAUGAAAUUUUAAAAGACAAUAGCCUAUAUUUGUGUCUCACUAAUAUAUAAAGUAUAGGUCAAAUUUAAAUUAUUUAAUUAGUUUUAAAUAUACACAAUUUGUCUCCUCUUUCAAACCUGACAUCUUCGGCUGUUUUAUUAGUCUUAAAUGAUGCAUUUACUUUGGUCAUUUUAUGCUAAUUUCUUCCAUAGUAAAUUAAUCAGGCUAUAUAAGGUAAUAUUUCCCCAGAGGGUAAUUUUAGUGGGACGAGGGUGGUGGGAUGAUGUCAUAUCAUACAUGGGAUUGCAUCAGAAGGGUUCUGUAAAGCCUGAACUCCCUUUUAAAAGUGCCUAGUGAUAGAGGCGUUGUUUGUCAUCUAUUAUAAUUGGAAUGUCAUUGUAGUUCAGUGAAUUUUGAUGUAAAUAAAAUAUCUUUUAAAAAUGUUAAAGUACCAGGAUAAACAAACAAAAAGAAACAACCCUUAAGAUGACAGAUUUUCCUCAACAUGCAGGUUUCCCUUCUUAUAUACCUCAAGUAUCCAACAUCUAGCCAUGCAAAUUGAUUACCUGAAGCAUAGUACUGGAAAGUAGAAUAGCAUGAAAAACUUAAUUUUGUGGACAUUACCUUUUUUUGUAAUCAGCUACUGUAUGUUUUAUUUUAGAUCUUUUGUUUUGGGUGGGUUUUCUGCUCUGGAGGUAUAUGCACUAACAAAACAUUUUCCUCCUUUCAUAUACGCAUGUUAAUUAGCAAUGUGAGCAAUAUUUCCUACCAUACUUCACUCCCAAUAUUUUUUGAGAUGUUUGUAUAAAAUGGAAUUUAAAGUUCACUUAUGAUUGUAUAUGAACCACAGAGGAGCCCAUUUAUUAAUAAAAAACUUUUUUAAUAGUUAAAUGUAGAGGGAAAAAAUAAAAAAAAAUGGGAAACAUUGUAAACAGCUUAAGUUUAUUUUGUGUAUGAUCGAGGCACUCUGUUGCAGGAAGGUGUGUAAUUGGGUUCUCUCUGCUUCAAAUGCGCUCUUUCAAACCAUUCAUUAUCCUGUGUAUUUUUAAUGUGGUUUUAGUAAAUGUUGGUAGUAGCUCUGUUGAAGUAGGUAAUUGUGUUAUGUUUUGGGUGGUACACACUUGGGGCAUGGUAACCCAAAUUUCAUGUGCACGGUUUCCCUUUAGCCCACUGCCCAAAUUUCACAUACCCUUCACCCUUUGUUCCCUUUGUAAAAGGAGUGGUAUCUGUUUUGAGCUGCCAAUUCAGAUGAUCAGAAAUGCUGCUUUCCUCAGCAUUGUCUUGUUAAACCGCAUGCCAUUUGGAACUUUGGCAGUGAGAAGCCAAAAGGAAGAGGUGAAUGACAUAUAUAUAUAUAUAUUCAAUGAAAGUAAAAUAUAUAUGCUCAUAUACUUUCUAGUUAUCAGAAUGAGUUAAGCUUUAUGCCAUUGGGCUGCUGCAUAUUUUAAUCAGAAGAUAAAAGAAAAUCUGGGCAUUUUUAGAAUGUGAUACAUGUUUUUUUAAAACUGUUAAAUAUUAUUUCGAUAUUUGUCUAAGAACCGGAAUGUUCUUAAAAUUUACUAAAACAGUAUUGUUUGAGGAAGAGAAAACUGUACUGUUUGCCAUUAUUACAGUCAUACAAGUGCAUGUCAAGUCACCCACUCUCUCAGGCAUCAGUAUCCACCUCAUAGCUUUACACAUUUUGAUGGGGAAUAUUGCAGCAUCCUCAGGCCUGACAUCUGGGAAAGGCUCAGAUCCACCUACUGCUCCUUGCUCGUUGAUUUUGUUUUAAAAUAUUGUGCCUGGUGUCAACUUUUAAGCAACAGCACUGCCUAAAAGCAAGCAGAGAACAGAAUCCCAGCACCAUUCUAUAGGCAACUUUUUAGAAUUCAGAUAUAGUAAAUCUGUUCCAGAUUUAUGAUGUUUUAUGUAAAAAAAAUUUUGUAUAAUAACAUAGCUGAAUAUUUUUGUUUCAUUUCUUUGAUGUAAGGCGUGUGAACAUUCGUUUGAAUAUCACAUGUUGAAGUCAGGUAUGGCACAAUGGGUUCUGAGACCAGCUUUUCCUCCCCUCCCAUUUGCCUUGUUCCAAGCUCUUUCUUUUCAAAUUACUUUUCUGAUAUUCAUAGGCAGGUAUUUAAUUUUACUAAUUAGCAUCCUGUGUGAAUGUAUUAAAGAAGCCACUGUGUUUUAGUGUAGUUGGCAAAAAUAUAAAAGCUGUUUCUUAUUUGCCCCUAUUUUUUUGGUGUCUUAAAGUUAUAUAUUAAAUCACAGAGAAGCAAGGGAGAAAGUUGAAAGAUAUCUAAGGCUCAUAUCACUUGAUUCUAUGGUAGAUUAUAUUAGAAUUGAGGAUGUGGCACAUUAAAACUGGAACAUGGGCAAAUAUAGUGUUCCAUUUUAAAAUUCUAAGUUUAUAUUGUUAAAUGGGUGAAAAUUUAAGUUUAUAUUUGCAUUUCCAAGCGUUUCUAAAAAUCACUAAUGCCAUCUAUACUUUUAGUAUGAAACAGCAGACUAUAGAAAGCACAGGGAAGAAUAGGCUAAAUACAUUCUUUGAAGAACCAGAGGCAUAUAACCACAUCAUUAUGUCAUUCCUAAUACAUGGCUAGAUUUUCUAAUGAUAAAAUUGACUGUGUCCCAAUGCUUAUUUGAUUCUAAGCUUUUUUAUUCUGUUUCUGAGAUAUUUUAAUAGCUUUGCAAAAUAUGCUGACCAGUUUUUGGAAAAUAAUGGUUUUUAUAGCAAGCAAAGACUUUAUGGCACAUUUUCAAAAUAGCACUCAUACAUACUUACAUUUUGACAGAAAUGUGAAUUCUCACAUUGAUGAGAUAUUCUUUUUCCCACCUGCCCUACCCUUUAAAAAAGGUCACUUUUCUAAUGUGUAGUAGAUUCAUUUACGCCUUUCCCUUUGAGUCAUACCAUGUUUGGAGAACUGUGUGAAUUGUAGGUAGAGAAAUUAACUAGGGAAGCCAGAAGCUUGAACUAAAGUUUUAAAUUUGUAGGCAGAUGAGAACUUUUAUACUAUGGUUGCUUUGGGCGAUUCUAAUUUUGUAAUAGCAUCAUGAUCACCAAAAUUAAUUCAAACAUUUUAGUACAUCUUUAAUCUGUCUUAUUUACCAAAGUUCUAAUCUGUUUAAGAACAGGAUGCCAAGAGCAUCUUUCAUUUUAUAGAAUGAUAUGCUCACCUUUAUAAGUGUCACCUAAAAGCUUGAGGGUAAAAAAGAAGCAGCCCAUAUAUCUAAACUACAGGAUGUCUUGAACAAGAUUCACAGAAAGAAAGAAAAAAAAGCAGUUCUUUCCAGGAAGGUGGUAAGGAAGAGCAUGCAUAUUUCUUGUUUUAACCAAAUACCUUUUUUAUGUAAAUGUCUCUAUUAAACCCCAGGUCCUACACCAGGAAAUAGGGUGAUAACCAGGAAAAUACCAAGCUUUAACCCAGUUGGCAGUUCCUUGUGGCAUACAUUUGGUUAGACUUGGGUUUUUCCUGGAACCAAAGGAAAAUAAGCAUGUUGAGUUCUUCGUUCAACAGACAUGACAUUGAAGUAAUAGAAUAUUUUUUAAGUAAAAUAGUUUUCACUUUCAAAGCCUAUGACAUAAGGACAUUUGUGCUUAUUAAUUGUUAAUUUUUUUUUAUGGUACAUUGUAUAAACUGAGUAGCAUUGAACUGCAUUUUAGAAGUAUGUCAUCAGAAACAAAUCACAUUAUGGAAAGGAUAUACAAAUGCCAAGUGAUAUGACUCUUUUGGCAUGGUGGUAGCAUGGUCCAUUCAGCUUUCAGAAUCUUUCGGAGGCUCUAGUUUGGUGCCUAGUACUAGUUAUUUUUGUUAGAACAAUCUCUCAAAAUUUAGAUAAUUUUCCAGUUGUAUGUCUGUCACUUUUAACUCUAAAGCGUAAGAAUCAUGGUAACCCUCUCAGAAGUGGUCCUUUCUUGCUCAUUUCAGUUUCGUAUUAACUUCAAAUCACUGAUGUAUUGUCUUUCAAGCUAUCAAUUGUUAUAUGUACCAAUUUAAUUUAGUUUGUAGUUAUCUGAAGUCACAAAAUUGGUUCAGCAUUGAUGUCAAACAAUGGCUUUGCUUCUUACCAAACAGACUUAGUAUCCUGCUGCUUGUUUCAAUCUUGAUGCAGUAAGUGAUGCAGUAUCUGGGUCUGUAUUUACUUAGAAACUGUACUGUCCUUUCUCUGUGCUUAACUUGCUAAAAAUAUAUUCCCUUACCUGUGAAAUUCCUGAGCGGUGCUCUGCCAACUUUUCAAGGGGAGGGAUUUGGAUGGCUGUGUUACUGCACACUGGAUCUGGAAUUGUUCAGGGUUAUGAGUGACAAAUUUCUUAAACACCAGCAGCACUGAGAUGUGCACUAUGGGCAUUCGUACAGUUGUUGUCCAAAUGCAAACAACUUUUUCAUCUUGGAGAAGCUGAGAUACAGAGUUCAAUAGAACUACUUGGAAUAUUUUGAGAAGGUUGAAUGUUUCAUCUUUGGCUUUGUUGUCUCUGGAGUGGGGAAGUAUGGAGGGCUUUUUUUUUUUUUUUUUUUUUUUUUUUUUUUUUUUUUAAAGAGAGUGUGUAUGUACUUUUUCUCUCUAUAAGGGCCAGGGUGUUGGUCAAAUUCACCAUCGAUUAAUUUAUAUCUUCUGUUGUGAUUUUUUUCAACUAUAUAACAAGUGCCAACUAAUUGUCCAUGGGACAAUCUACUUUUCCACUCAAUUUAUCGUUUUGAGUAGGGAAAGGUUCAUUUAUUUUCAUUACCUGGCAUUAAGUUAAAGAAUUCAUUAUUUUGCAUACAUUUGAGUCAUUCUGUGACCUAUAAAGUGUUUUUGUAACUAUCUAAUUCUAAUGGUUGCAAAGCAAAGCACAUGACUGUAAAACCAAGCAAGGUGUUUUAGUAACUUUUUCCCUGAAUACUUGGUAGUUUCCAUUGAUACUAUUCCAAAACAAAUUCUGCUGUUUUAGGUUGUAUAUUUACUUUGCUUUUGUUCUAAGAAAAAGCCAAGGACUAAAUCAACUUGUUUUUGUGUUUCAGUAAUCAGUUUAAAAUCUAAGAUUUUUUUUUAAAUUAGACUAUUUAAUGAAGUGCCAUGUAAUUGUAGCUUGCUAGUGUUUAAUGUUUAAUAGACUGGUUCUGUAGGUGUUUUAACCAUUUAACACUCUCUGCCAUCCCUGGAGAAAGUGGUUCUACUCUUACUGAACACAUUCUCUCUGACAAAAUCACCAGCUGCUUUAUUUUUCUAUUUAUUACAGUUAAACAGUUGAUGAGGUCUGAAUCUUGACCAAAACUGCUCAGCUGAGAUGUUUUUCACAAUAGACACUGUACAAAGUGUGCGUGCAAAAGGACACGGUUGGUAGUAUUUUUUCAUUAAUGUGAACAUUGACUAAAAAAAAGCAGUCCUGCCUUUUAAAUCUUGUGGCAGCUCAGAAGGGAGGUGCUUAAGAACCUUAACUACUAUGUCAGAUAACAAAAUAUUUUUUUCCAUUUUGGAGAUUGGUUACUGCUCACACAUGAUGUAUAGGGCUAAAUAUAUGCUUGUUUCCUUGCACCUGUGUACUUCCCCUCUCUCCCUCCCUUUCCUUCCCCUGUAGGCAAUAAAUGGCCAUUUUGCAACUGCA